AGUCAGAGGAGAAAAUGAGGUCCAGCUCGUCCCUGGCUCUCUCUCUCUCUCAGGUCCUGAUGUCUUUUCCAAGUCUGGAGAGCAGCGAUGCUGCCUGUGCCCUGCGCAGAAAACCGUGUUCCGGCUGCAGCUAACCACCGCAGGCUCAAUGUCUCUGGGUGUAUCUCAGAGAUAAGCAGGAGGCAUACACGGAAUACCUGAGGAGCAUCCACUAUAUCUCCCAGGUGUUACUAGAAGAAGUGGAAACCACUAAAGAAGCUGGGGAAACUGUGCCCCCCGACACCUCCAAGAUGCUGAAGCUAGCACAGCAGUGUCUGGAGAGGGCCCAGUCGACGGCCGCCAAGCUUGGGAAAACACGCCUGAAGCCAACCAUGCCUGCAGCUGCUCCCAUUCCCCAGCCUGCCGGCCGACACCGCCGUGUAUACUCCGAUGAAGGAGGAAAGCUCUCUCCUUUUCUGCCACCCGAGAUCUUCCAGAAGCUUCAGGGGGCAGAGUCACAAAGCUGUAAGAAAGAGCUGACGCCACUGGAGGAGGCCUCCCUGCAGAAUCAGAAGCUGAAGGCUGCGUAUGAGGCCCGAAUGGCGCGGCUAGACCCCAGCCAGGCCAUGCAGAAGACAUCCCUGACCCUCUCUCUACAGCGGCAGAUGAUGGAGAACCUAGUGAUUGCCAAAGCCCGGGAGGAGACACUCCAGAGAAAGAUGGAGGAGCGCCGGCUGCGGCUCCAGGAGGCCGCCAACAGGAGGUUUUGCAGCCAAGUCGCCCUGACCCCGGAGGAACGGGAGCAGCGGGCCCUUUACGCCGCCAUCCUGGAGUACGAACAGGACCAUGACUGGCCGAAGCACUGGAAGGCCAAGCUCAAGAGGAAUCCGGGGGACCUGUCACUCGUGACCAGCCUGGUCUCACACCUGCUCAGCCUCCCCGACCACCCGAUCGCGCAGCUCCUGAGGCGGCUGCAGUGCUCCGUGUACAGCGCCCUGUAUCCCGCCGUGAGCAGAGCAGCCGCGCCAGCCCCAGGCUGCUGCCCCCCGACCCCCAACCCCGGAAGCCGACGGCUGCGGCCCUCGCAGAGCCUCCAUUGCAUGCUGUCCCCGCCCGAGCCCAGCGCAGCCCCGCGGCCCCAGGACAGUCCCCCCACGCCCCCACUCCAACCCGGCCCCGUGGGGUCUCCCUCACCCCUGGGGGACACCGCAUCUGGAUUGCCAGACAAGGACAGCUCGUUCGAGGACCUGGAGCAGUUCCUGGGGACGUCUGAGCGGCAGGGCCGGGGCCGUGGGGUACAGCCGGAGCCCCAGCUGCAGCAGCUGAAGACCGCGGUGGAGGAGAUCCACAAUGCCGUAGGGGAGGAGCCUCUGUGGACGUCCCCGGCUCUGUUCCUAGCAGACAGGCUGCUCUCGCUGACCCUUCUGGCCUUCGAAGGCCUAAACACAGCUGCCUCCAAGGACCGCUGCCUGGCCUGCAUUGAGGAACCCUUUUUCUCCCCGCUGUGGCCUCUGCUGCUGGCCCUGUACAGGAGCGUGCACCGAGCCCGGGAGGCUGCCCUGAGCAGGAGCAUGGAGCUCUACAGGAAUGCACCCCCCACCGCCAUUGGCAUCCCCACCAAGCUCCUCCCCCAGAACCCUGAGGCCAAGGGGGCCACUGGCUACCCCUACUGCGCGGCGGCCCAGGAGCUCGGACUGCUGGUCCUGGAGAGCUGCCCCCAGAAGAAGCUGGAGUGCAUAGUGCGGACCCUGCGGAUCAUCUGUGUCUGUGCGGAAGACUACUGCCCCACCCCAGAGGCCACACCCCAGGCCGGGCCCCCGCCCAUCGCUGCAGCUGCCAUUGGUGCCGAUGACCUGCUGCCCAUCCUGUCCUUCGUGGUGCUGAGGAGCGGCCUCCCUCAGCUGGUGUCGGAGUGCGCGGCCCUGGAGGAGUUCAUCCACGAGGGGUACCUGAUCGGAGAGGAGGGCUACUGCCUCACAUCACUGCAGAGUGCCCUGAGCUACGUGGAGCUGCUGCCCCGGGGAGGCCUGGCCAAGUAGUACAGCUAGAGCCCAGGGUCCCUGCAGGGCCUGGCCUCGCCUCCCAGGGCUGUCUCUCCUACACCUGGAGCCAUGGGAUCUACUGAGGACCAUCCUGGAGCCUCACGCUGCUCUGCACAUGGUGGGGGCUUGUCCACUGUGGUGUGCUCUCCAGCUCUUCACCUUCCUCACCUCACAUCUGACCCUGGAGCUUGGGGUUGGCACCUCUGCCCCGACAGAAUGGGGCUGAAUCAGCUCCAGGAGGAACCAGGCCCUGCUCUCCUGUGUAGGCCUCAGAGAGGCCAAGAAGGGAAGCUUUGGGCUUCGGUGGGUGCAGGCUCAGCGAUGAACAUCUGGCUGGGGCAGCUCCUGGGGAGCAUCAGGGAAGAGGGGGCCAUGAGCCGGCCAGCAGUGGAGACGGCAGUCCAGUUUCUCUCCCCUCUGACCCCUAGAAGGGGAGUUGUAGCCCCAUGAACUAGUUUCUUGUCUGGGUCAGGAACAAGGGCCGGCUGGGGCCUGGGGUGCAGCUGGUGUCAGGGUAUGCUGUUUGCUGAUGGGCAGGGACACCCCUGCAGGGUCUCGGGCUCUGAGCCCAGGACAUUCCCUGCCCCUUACUCACCUUGGCUGUGGGCUGUGAACAUUCCGGGACCCUGGGCAUCUUAUCUAGGUCCGUGCAGCCCAAGGGUCAGCCCUCUUGACUGUCACAUGCUGCCCCCACCCAGCCUAAAAUAAAGAGCUCACUGCUGUG